AUGGCUCUCCACUUGUCCCGAGUGUCACGACGACGAGGAUGGGGACCAUAUCUUCGGAGCCUGAGGAUCCAACACAGGUCCAGCCCUGUGCAGCCGCCCGCCAAGCCGCCAGAGGACGAGCCGGACGCCGAAGGCUACGAGUGGACGAUUGCAGUUAGUUUCCAACUCGCCGACUUCGCGCCCCUCCACUGGCUCCGGCUUGAUGAUCCCGGCUUCGGGGUGCUCUCGACCGGACCAGAGAGGUGGGAAGUUUGGGGGCACCCGCUGUGGGUGUCCCGUUUCCGGGGCUGGGCUCCGGGGAGCCGGCGCGGCGCCCGCUCCCUGCCCGCCAGCCCUUUGGGAGCUCAGGCGCGGGCAGCCGCUUGUGUUCCUGGGAAGGGCGGAGCUGCGUCCCGGGGAGACACGCCUUGCAGCCGGCAGCCUAGUCGCUCCCCGCUGGCCGGCCGCUCCGUGAGGGCCCCGCAGCGGAGGGUCGGGGCUGGGGCGGGCUGGAGAGGGGGCCCCGGGCUGGGGCCGGUUCGGCCUCCCGGGUGGCGCGCGGGCCGAAGAACUAGGAGGACCGCCGGGCCGGGCCGCUUGUCCUUUGGAAAAACCUUGGCGGUUCCUCCUCUGGUGUCCGUGGACCCCGCCGUGGCGUUCUCCAGGGCCGCGGACCUUUGCCCACCGGUCGCGCCAGCUGUCCUGGAGCAGAAAGGACCCCCCUCCUCCCGGACCGAGCCCCGAGCCCCGAGCCCCAUGGAGCAGGCAAGCGCCGGAGUCCCGAGGCUAAGGCCCGGCCGGCGGGCGCUCUGGCACCUUUUCCCGCCCCCGAGGGUGCCUGUCCGGCCCGGCCGGGACUGGCUGGGAAACCGAGGCCGGAAGAGGUCGCAGUCCAGCAAGGAAUCGGGGCAGCUCUUCCGUGGUUCCUUGCAGACCCCAGGUCAGGCCAGAAAACACCUCUAUGGCCCUUCCCUGUGUCCCACCACCAGAUAGGACCUCAAAGGCCUGGGGUCCCCAGGAUGGCCCUCAAACCGACUGGUGCCCUUGCAGGCUGCCACCCUCCAAGUCCUGCUUCUCUCUAGAGAUGGGCAGGAGCACCAGCCCUCACCUGGCACCAGCAGUGAGUCUCAUAAUUGCCAUCUACCAUUUUGCUAGGGGGCUUCUGGGGAUCCUAGGAAAAGCAGCAGAUGCCUGGGUGCUUGGGGACCUGGGCAUUCUGAGGGAAGGAGCAGCGUGACCCUGAGUCAUUUUUCACUGGGGACAAAUGAGCCAACUCCUUCUACCCAGUGAUAAAAUCAGAAGGAAGCAGAUGGAGACAGCACUGUUCAGGGGAUGAUUUGGGGAUGAGAAGAACUGGCAGGAAGUUGGGGAUGUGGGGGUGAGAAGAACCAGCAGGAAGUUGGGGAUUUCUUGUUUCCCCACUUUUCCCUUCCAUUUCUGUUUGAGCCUUAGGUUUGGCCUCCGUCUCCCUCUGUAGGAAUUGCAGCUAAUUAAAUAUUCUGCCUCUUAUUCCAGCUUUACUGGUGGAACAUAAUAUGGUCUAAGAAGAGAUUUUUGCAGCAAGAGGCCAUCUCUGCAAAUCACCUGUGAGGCAGACCUGUGGCAAUUUUAUGACUCAGCUGGCCACCGGGAUUGUAGCUGGGUUCUGCCGCUUGUUGAAACCUACUCAAUGUUCUCCUUCCCUAAGUAGGACAAGACCGUAUCCUGCCUUUAAGGUUUAUAGAAUAAAAACUGAAAACUCUUUGGGGAAGAAAAUCUUCCUGAACAGAUAGCCCAGGGCAUUUUGAAAAUCCCUUAGGAAGUUCUCUGUUUCACUUGGGUACCUUUGUCCUUGGACUUUGGUGAUGUGGUUUGACCCCAGCUAGAGAGUGAGGGGAACAACAGCAAAAGGCAGGACAAAGACUGACUCGUGAGAGGAGGCCCAGGAACAGGGGGCCAUUGUGAAUGAGGAGGACGUGGGGGCCCAAGAAAGUGAGCAAAAGAGGACAGGGCUUGCGCACUCAGUCACCAGCCCCCUUCUGGGGUCCAAGCUGUGUCCCCUUCUCUAAAGAGGUAAGCCCUGAGUCAUGGGAAGAUGGAAACCGGGGCUCAUGAGACAGGAUGUUUUUUAAGCACCGUGGUGUCUUGUUGACUUGCACAUGCACGGGGGUCUUGGGUAACCACAGGGCUCAGGGUAUUUGCAGGAACAGUUCAAGUGCUCACUUGUCUUGGGGCUGUUUAUGGGGAAGUGGUUUCCACAGUGAGAGGAGGUGAGAUAUUGUUGUCACCCCGGACGACACUUAGCUAGUUCCUUCUCACUAAAGCUCUGUAGUCAUAUUUUCCCUGGCAGAGCAGAAACUUCUAUGUUAUCCCACAGCUGUUCUAACGGUGUAGACUUGACUUAUGCAAUGAUGCCAGGAGUCCUGAGCAGCACAGCCCAACUUCAAUCACACACAGAUGGACAGAGCUGUAUUAGCAAAGCCUGAGCUACUGAGCGAUGAGAGUACAGCCAGGCUUUCAGACAUCUGUU